CCUUCAGCAUAAAAGCUGAUCCACAAACAAGAGGAGCACCAGACCUCCUCUUGGCUUCGAGAUGGCUUCGCCACACCAAGAGCCCAAACCUGGAGACCUGAUUGAGAUUUUCCGCCUUGGCUAUGAGCACUGGGCCCUGUAUAUAGGAGAUGGCUACGUGAUCCAUCUGGCUCCUCCAAGUGAGUACCCCGGGGCUGGCUCCUCCAGUGUCUUCUCAGUCCUGAGCAACAGUGCAGAGGUGAAACGGGAGCGCCUGGAAGAUGUGGUGGGAGGCUGUUGCUAUCGGGUCAACAACAGCUUGGACCAUGAGUACCAACCACGGCCCGUGGAGGUGAUCAUCAGUUCUGCGAAGGAGAUGGUUGGUCAGAAGAUGAAGUACAGUAUUGUGAGCAGGAACUGUGAGCACUUUGUCACCCAGCUGAGAUAUGGCAAGUCCCGCUGUAAACAGGUGGAAAAGGCCAAGGUUGAAGUCGGUGUGGCCACGGCGCUUGGAAUCCUGGUUGUUGCUGGAUGCUCUUUUGCGAUUAGGAGAUACCAAAAAAAAGCGACAGCCUGAAGCAGCCACAAAAUCCUGUGUUAGAAGCAGCUGUGGGGGUCCCAGUGGAGAUGAGCCUCCCCCAUGCCUCCAGCAGCCUGACCCUCGUGCCCUGUCUCAGGCGUUCUCUAGAUCCUUUCCUCUGUUUCCCUCUCUCGCUGGCAAAAGUAUGAUCUAAUUGAAACAAGACUGAAGGAUCAAUAAACAGCCAUCUGCCCCUUCA